AACUUCCGGCGUCCGUCGGGCAGCAGCGGGGCUGUCUAUCCCGGCUGAGGACCCGCGGCCAGUGCGGGUGGCUGGCUUUGCCAUUAGCGGGGGCCUUUCCUGAGGACGGCGUACGGAGUGUGGGGAAUGAAGGAUGGCAGCAUGCCGUGCAUUAAAAGCUGUUUUGGUAGAUCUCAGUGGCACACUUCACAUUGAAGAUGCAGCUGUGCCAGGCGCACAGGAAGCUCUUAAAAGGUUACGUGGUGCUUCUGUAAUCAUUAGGUUUGUGACCAAUACAACCAAAGAGAGCAAGCAAGACCUGUUAGAAAGGUUGAGAAAAUUGGAAUUUGAUAUCUCUGAAGAUGAAAUAUUCACAUCUCUGACUGCAGCCAGAAGUUUACUAGAGCGGAAACAAGUCAGACCCAUGCUGCUAGUUGAUGAUCGGGCACUACCUGAUUUCAAAGGAAUACAAACAAGUGAUCCUAAUGCUGUGGUCAUGGGAUUGGCACCAGAACAUUUUCAUUAUCAAAUUCUGAAUCAAGCAUUCCGGUUACUCCUGGAUGGAGCACCUCUGAUAGCAAUCCACAAAGCCAGGUAUUACAAGAGGAAAGAUGGCUUAGCCCUGGGGCCUGGACCAUUUGUGACUGCUUUAGAGUAUGCCACAGAUACCAAAGCCACAGUCGUGGGGAAACCAGAGAAGACGUUCUUUUUGGAAGCAUUGCGGGGCACUGGCUGUGAACCUGAGGAGGCUGUCAUGAUAGGAGAUGAUUGCAGGGAUGAUGUUGGUGGGGCUCAAGAUGUCGGCAUGCUGGGCAUCUUAGUAAAGACUGAAACAAGAAAUGUAGAUGGAGCUACAAUUGAAUAAGAAGUAUGUGGCAAAGGUCUGCACAAAGAGUGAAAACACUGUCUGCUUGCUCCUGGGGCCUGAAGUGAACCAUUGGAGCCUUGCAGAUAGUAACACCAGUCACUCUAGAAUUAACACAGUGGAUUUUUUCGAAUGUCUCAGUCAAAAUGAUCACCUUCCCAGGAACGUAACAGCCCUGUGAUGUAAGCAGAAAAGAGGAAGAAUGAAAUGAAGUCUGGAAAAGUAGCCACACUCGUCAGCCUCCAUGUAUCUUUGUUUUCAGAUUCCUGCCUUUUGCUGUUUUAUUUUCUCAUUAUUGAAGAAAUCCUUAGAUAACUAUUUUUGCUCUUGUGUAUUAUUCCCAUGAGUAUUUCUUUCUUUCUUUCUUUCUUUUUUUUUUUUUUUAGCUCAUGUAAUUAAGGAUUUACACUGAGCUUCAAAAUGGUACCUCUGUCAGUGUCUUGAUGGGCCCAGCUCCCCCAGCUGGUCUCCACUGGCUCUGUCGUCUAUUGUGACUGGCAUUUUAUUGUGACCAGCCUUUCACAGGCAUCAGUUUAGUCUCUGAGAAGCCAUCAGCGUAACACAAUCAAGUCCAAAAUGUGUAAUUAGUAAAUCAACUAAGUACAGCUCUUGGAAGCAGGCAUAUUUGUACCAUUGAUUUUUGGUCAGAAAAAUCAUGAAUAACCCUACUGUUCUAAAAACAUGUGGAACAGCCAGCUUCAUUGGUAAAUUUUAACUCAGUGCAGUGGACAAGUGCUAGGCUUCCCAGUGUUGAAAAUAACCGUAAAUAUUUUAAUUCAUAUUCAAUAAUAAGUGCUUUCUGUGGAUCAUCUCGAGCAAUUUUGUUUCUAAAGGGGUAGCACAAGGUAGAUGCUCAAUAUAAUUUGAUCAAUUAUUUGUUAAAGAUUUUUGACUAGUCCUAACCAGAAUUUGUUUAGCAUGUGAAACAGUCAUCUAGAAAAAAAAUAGGAUCUUUCUUUGCCUUCAUAUAUCAUCAACAUAGCAUCCUGUUUUCUCCCUCCAUUCAUCAUUUAUCCAUCCAUGAAAGCACAGGCUGCUGCAGUGAGUGAAUCAGCCAUGAGCAAUGCAGGCAGCUCCAUUCACUCAACGAACGUUAUUGAGCCCCUGCUGUGUGCUAGGUGCUAGAACUAAAACAUAUACCUAAGCCACUUUUGUCAAUUUCUAUUUUGUAGAAACCCCACUUGCAGAGCCAGACUAAGCAAAAGCCUUUAACUCCAUGGCUAGGAAGCUUAUUUAUUUGUCUCUUAGACCACUGGAUCCAGAAAGUAGGUCAUAUAGUAAUAUUUAGUCAUUAACUUACCUGUAAGAUCAAAUAGAAACCUUGUGAAGGAGUUUAUACUAACGAUAUUUAAGCUUGGGAAGAAAACUGGCAGUAGAGCUUGCUGCGGGGACCAUGCUAUGGACAGGUGCCUUCAGGGUGCUAACGAGAGUGAGGUAUAUAUUAAUUACCUUUGUACAUUUGAUGCUGGCUCCCUUCCUGUAAGAAGUUAUAAUCAGUAAGAUAAGACAGGAAGCGUCUUCUCCACCAUGAUGCAAAGAUGUGGAAAAGAGGGUUUUUCAGGCUUUGUGUUUGUCUGGCAAAGCCUCUUAAAGUAGUUGUAGAAAACAGUAGGUCUCUUGUUGAAAGAGCUGAGUUUAGGCAGAGAAAACUGGGAAAAGCAGAAGAAUCAACAAUAGAGACCACAAAGGGAUGAGAGAGCAAGGAGAAAGGUGAAGGGCAGAGGCAGCCCUGGUGGCUACAGGGCAGGAGCUGCGUUCUGCAUUUCCUCCCUCCCCUCUCUUCUUCCCUCCAUUCAUUCUUUAAAAAGAUAUUUAUAGGAUAGUUACUAUGUGCUAGUCACUAUGUUAGGUACUUGGAAUACAUUGGGACAUGUAACAGAUAUAGCCCCUGUCUCAAAUAACUUAGUCUUCUUAAAUGUGAGACAGAUGUUAAACAAAUAAAUGCAUAAUUACAAAUUGUUGUAAAUGUUGUGGAGGCAAAGAACAAGGUGAAUAACAGGGAGGGGGUUUAAUUUGGAUGGGAAGGUGGGGUCUGACCUGAAGCAUGAAGGAGGUAGUCAGGUGAGAAUAAUGGAAUGACAAGGGAAUGGCACGUGUGUAGGCCCUCAGAAAAGCAGGUCCAGUCUGGGACUGCAGCCUGGUGAGCCAGUAGCACAUGCUUAGGUGAGAGGGUCACUGGGGCUGCAUGACAAAGGGCUUGGUAAGCAGCAGUAGAGAUUUUGGAUUCUUUCUGAAGGGCACUGGGACCCAUUAAAGGGUCUUUAAAUAGGGACUGUGCACCUUCUGACUUGUAAAAGCUCUUUGUGACCACUGUGGAAUGGUUCCUCUGCUGUGUUGAGGUGUUAAAUUGUGUGCCAGGUGCUAGAACAGCAGGCCAUCUUGAAUUCCACGGUUGGGAGAGUCAGGCAGUGAGCCUGCUGCUUGAUGCCAAGUGGCCUGUCCUGCCUGGCCCCUGGCCUGCGAGCAUCCAUCACUCUUUUCCUCCCCAACCCAGGGCGUUCUCAUCUGCUGGGCUCCCGGGCUGCCUGGAUCCCUGCGUGGCAGCAGCACAUCCUGUUCCCAGUUGCCUUUGGGAGCGGAUGAGUCCUCUGCCCUCUGGGGUCUGGGCUUCCAUUUUAAAGCAUUAAUUUAAUCACCAAUCUAUCUUUAGAGCUGAGGGUAGGGGAAAGAAAAUGAUUUCAUCAGCUGUGAACAUGUGAAGGGAAUCUUAGCUGUCAGACGAUCCAGUACCUGUGGCUGUCCAUUGUGAAUGACCAGAGGGCCUGGGGAAAGGCUGAAUGUGACAUUUCUUUGAAUUGCCUCAUUUACAUCCUGAAGCCUCAAUAAAAGGUGAUUUGGGAGAUGUGCAGCCCCUGAUUCUGUCUUAACUGUAAGGGUGGUGCUGUGAUGACCCAGGUGCUCAUGGGGUAUGAUUAAUUUAGCAUUCUGGUGGCAGCCUGUGUUUACUGGCUUUACUUUCAUUUCAGGGAAAUAUCGAGCAUCAGAUGAAGAAAAAAUUAAUCCACCUCCUUACUUAACUUGUGAGAGUUUCCCUCAUGCUGUGGACCACAUUCUGCAGCACCUAUUGUGAAGCAGUGUGUGCAUCUGAAGCAACUUGAAAUGCAGCUUCUUAUUGUCUGGAAUGAAUCCCUUACCAACUCAGUGCCAGCAUCGGUAGACACCAGUCAGUGCUGAUCGCUUUUUAACCCUCUUUUGUUGUGCAUUAAUUAGAAAGAAAGGUAUUGAAUUGCGGCUAGCCAGUAAGCCUUGCUAAUCUCUUUUAUUUUGUAACUGAAGAUGAGACCCAAAGAAAGGGAAAGCUGAGAUUUUGUGCCAUUCCUUUUAAAAUAUUCAUCAGGUUAGGUGGGGCUGUGGGGGAAAAGCUACUACAGGGAAGAGUGUUCUCUGCUGUCUCUUCACUGGAAAACAGGGAGGGGGGAUUUCAGACUGUGAAGAAAGUUGAAUGGUGGUUUUUAAAUUAUAAAGUAAUGUAUUAAAAGGUGCAUUAGGCUGUAGUUCUAAUAUUGAGUUCAACUGUGAAAUCCAUCAGAUGUGCCAAAUGGAGAAGACAGAAAGCAACAAAGUGAAUUGUUCUUUAGCCCAAGUGGUACAGUGAAUUUGCUUUAACAGAUGUUGAAAACUAAAUUUUCUACUGUAUUCCCAGCACGGGUGACUUCUUUUUCUCUUCAUUAGCCAGAGAUGACUAAUUUAAAUUUAGAACCAGAUUUUAAUUUAAAUUAAUAUUUCCAUUAAUAACCUAUUCAUUGCAGAUACCUAUUAUACUGUGUAACAGUUGUUUUGGAAAUUUUAUGUAAAAUUAAAACUAUCAGUAUUUUACAGAUGUUUUAAUUAGACAUUGUUAUUAACAGGAACAGUGCAGAAACUAGAAUCAAGCCUUAUAAUAUCUUAUAGACCAUGCAUUUUUGAAGUUAGUGUCCACUAGGGUCCUAUUAACUGUACAUUUGCAAGAUUUCAUUAUUUUUGCCUCUGACACUAUGGGAAAAAUUUUUUAGAAGCUAUUGGGACAGAUUCAAGCUUUUAUGCACUUGGUUACUACAGCUGUAAAAUGAAAUCUCGUCUUGUAGCAUGGAUUAUUCUUCUCAUGUUAAACCCACCAAAAUAAAGGGGACUAAAUAGGUAAUGAUUUUCCUAGUGCAUUUGCAUACUGUGAUAAUCCUGGGCCUUGCAAUAGUUCUACAGGGCUCUUGGGCAUUGAAUUAUUAGGAUGUAAUUGUACAUCAUUGUAGUGUUCACCUUAUUGAAGCUCACUCUGAUGUUAAUGAGCUUCGGGUUUUGAUGCUUGUUUAGAGAUCAGCAGUCUUGGAUGGGAGGGAACAAAGCUAAAUAAAUGUUAGUUUGGUGA